AGGGCAGGCGGGCGGCUGGCAGCUGUGGCGCCGACAUGGCUGCGCUGGUGGAGCCGCUGGGGCUGGAGCGGGACGUGUCCCGGGCGGUUGAGCUCCUCGAGCGGCUCCAGCGCAGCGGGGAGCUGCCGCCGCAGAAGCUGCAGGCCCUCCAGCGAGUUCUGCAGAGCCGCUUCUGCUCCGCUAUCCGAGAGGGCUGGAGGAGCUGGCGACUCCCUGAUGCCGCUGCCUCCUCACCCAGGUGUAUGAGCAGCUUUAUGACACGCUGGACAUCACCGGCAGCGCCGAGAUCCGAGCCCAUGCCACAGCCAAGAGCGUUGAGGGUGAGCAGCAUGAGAAGGCGGUGGAGCUGCUGAAGGCGGCCCAGGGCUCGGUGAAGCUGGUUGUCCGUUACACACCGCGAGUGCUGGAGGAGAUGGAGGCCCGGUUCGAGAAGAUGCGCUCUGCCCGCCGGCGCCAACAGCAUCAGAGCUACUCGUGAGCCCCUGGGUCACCACACCCCUGGGGCCUCCACGGGCUCCCUUUAACCCCAGGCUCCCAAACCAGGCCAGUGCUUCCUGGAUCUUCCAGCCCUGGCCCCUCCUCUGGGAUCCUGACCCUUGACCCUUGGCCCAGGCUCUCACCCCAGGCUAGUUUGGCCAAAUCCCCUGGGGAGCCCUUAGCUUCCUUCCAUCCCAAGAUACGGAACCUACUGUGGCUGGGAUCCCUCAGCCCACUUACCUGGGCCCUUGCCUCUGCAACCCCAGUCCUGCCCCUCUUGUCUACCCGGAGCCUCCCUGAUCCCGGGUCCCUUGUCCACCCCCCUUGCAGGUCCUUGGAGUCUCGAGGUUGAAACCACAGAUCUGGACGUUCACGUGCACUCUCUUCCUGUACAGUAUUUAUUGUUCCUGGCACUUUAUUUAAAGAUAUUUGACCCUCA